GUGAGUGUGUACUGUCCUAAGCUCAGACCUGGGAAGGCUGUCAUAAUGUGAAUUUAGGCCAUCUGGUCAACUCCCAGCCUGGAAGCUAUUGGGUGCCAGAAAUAUCUAUACACUAGAGAUGCAGUGAUCUGUUAAUACCAAGUUAUCAGGUUUUGCUGUGGCUGCAAAUUUCAGCAAUAUCCAAACCAGCCAGUUUUGGCUCUAAGGCUUUAUCUGCCCUCAAACUGCUGACAAGGAUGGAAAGAGAAGCAAUAGUUGGGGAAGAAUAAGACAAAAUGUGGAGGGACACAAGAUGUCUUCUGUGAGAACCAAGGAAAUGACGACGUACCGGAAUGAAGUCAGCCUCCCAAUAGGCCAUUGACACUGGAUCCAAGGAGUCUGGAAACGUUUCUUGACGUGCGUUUCACUGACCCAGAUGGAACCUCGGGUGAUGUGUUUCUCUUUUCCUGAUGGGUCUUAUGGAGCAUGCCAUGUGCAGGCCUUCUCUUAGAGAAUGUUUUCCUAAUUUUGUUUUUCAGUCUUUGUAUGCCAUUGGCUGGAACAUGCCAGACUCUUUUUUAAAUAAAUGUUUAGAGAAUUUUACACUCAGAGCUCCUUUGAGAGCAGGCAGCCUGUUUUAACCUUAGAUAACCGUCUUCCUGUGCCUCUACCUUUAAGUUCUUCUUAUAUUCACACCUAGCAAUGAGAGAUAUGAAAGAAGAUAGGUUUUAGGUUUAGAAACACCUCGCUCAUUUACUGACCUAACUGCUUAAUAGUUCUAUGAACUUCAAGCUGGCUACUUAAUCUUUCUGAACUUCAAUUUCUUUAUCUGGUUAAAAUGGAUAACUGUGUGGUAAAGUCCAAAUAAAAUCGUGAAAGUUAAGUACCUGUCAUAGUAUUUGGCAUUUUGUGAGCACCUGGUAUGUCUUCAUCUCCUUCCUUCAUUUAGGCUAAAGAUGGAUAUUGUUCCCUUCUGAUAAGUGCCAGCAUUAGUGCAUACUGACAUCUGCCAUGUUUGCUGAGUAAACACACUGGUGAUUAGAAUAUUUCUAAUGUGUGAGCAUGUUCCUUGCAUUGCUUUUGAGAACAUGUUCAUUAAUUAGAAGUACAGUUGCCAAAAGAAGAUAUCCCCAAUAAGCUGAGAACAGUAGCUUGUAUUGACUAAGAGUCCAGGCUGAUGAAUCAGAUCUCCUGGCUUUAAACUGAGCUCAGUGGCUUUGUGACCUUGGUCACGUAAUUUAACUUCCCAGACCUGUUUCUUCUGUAAGAUGGAGGUAGUAAUACUUCCAAUUUCUUUGGUUAUUCUGAGGAGUGAAUGAGACAAUGUAUGUGGAACCCUUAGCAUAGUAAUAGUUAGCUUUUAUUGAUCACUUACUGAUAGUAUUGUUAAGCAUGUUGGAAAUGAAAAUGUAGACAUAGAUACAUUAUUUACAUAUUGCAAAGUUUAUACAGCCUGAAAGCUAAUCUGUGUGAAGUGCUAGUUGAAUUAAAUGUUGAGGGAGAAGUAACUGAAUUUUCUUCUGGUUUGAAGUAUUUUACCAAUGUUUCAACCUGCACAAUUGUAUGUGAACAUACAUUAGGACUUUGGGGGCAGAAUUCCAUAAACUCUGUGAGAAGGCUUAAAGUGGCAGACACUCAACUCAAAGUCACUUAAGAGAAAAAGGGAGGAGAGAGACCUAUGUCACAUAACUUGAAAAGUCUAGUGUUUGAAAGAAUACAAUAUGACUAGAUCCGGGUAAUCUCACAGUGUCACUAGAAAUUAGUCUCAGUUGUAUCACCUGGUUCUGCUUUAGCCUUAUUCUCAAGAAGGUUCUCCCCAGGUGGUGACAGAGAUAGCCAUCAGUAGCUCCGGAAUGAUAUCCUGCCAGCCAGGCAACUUCUGCAGUCAAAGAGGUGCUUUCUCAAAGGUUCCAGCAAAAGCCUCAAGAUUGCAUCUCAUUGGGCCACUUUGGGUCAUAUACCUGGUUCUACACCAGUCACCGCAGGGAUCUGUGCAUGAGGGGUGGGAGGUGCGAAUAUGAAAGUCAGCCCGUGUGUGGAAGUAUACAGAGUUAGCACCAAGCUAGGAUAAUGCAGUCCCUUUACAGGGACAUCAGAAAGGAAGGAGAGCUCCCACUUCUGGGACAAGAAGCACUAAUGCAGUCAUUUUACUGUUUGCUUUUUUCUUUCUUUUCUGAAGGACUAUUUUUAAAUCUGAAUUUUUUGUUUUUGUUUUUCAUCAGUCUGUUCAUACAUAAGGCGACGUAGACCCUGAGUGUCUGGCCUCAGUCCUACCAGAUAACAGCCCUUCCCAGUUGCUAGUACAAAUAUUAGGUUUCCACGUGGAGGAAUUCUGUAGGCUGUUCAAACCUGUGAUAAUCAGUGAGCAGCCACAUGGCCUGAAACAAAUUCCUCGUUCUUGUAAUUGCACAUAAUCUUUGCUGGUAUGCACAGAACUUCUACCUCUAUUUGUGAGUGUCUGGAGCAACCAGGGGUUUAAAACCACAGGGUACUGCUUAAGCUGCACUAUUGUCAUGUGCAUGGAGAUGUUUAUUUUGAGUGAGACAUUUUGCUAAGGUCACCAGAGGUUGUAAUUGCAUGAAUAAAGGGAACGCUGCUUCCCAUACUAUACUGCUGCUGUUUUUUCCAGUGAGUGUAUUUAGCCUAAGGGCUCAUUGUGUGUGGUUUGGAACAGGCAGGAUUCUUUUUUUUUUCCCCCUCAGGUGUGAGAUAGCCAGAUCUGAAAUACAGUUUCUCAGCUUAGCUCAGGCUUUAUCCUCAAAUUCUGUUUUAUGUUUUAAUGAAAAGAAGAGAAUGCUUGUGGCAAGAGCAUUGCCACCACAAUGUCACUAGAAAUUAGUCUCAGUUGUAUCACUUGGUUUUAGUUCUAGUUCUAAUUUUAGUUCACACUGCUCCUUCUCUGAUUCUGAUCAUAGCCCAAGCCAGCAUCUUGCUGCUUGUUUUAAGUUGUGGAAAUGAUUACCGACAGUCAUUCUGUAAGACCUAGGGACUUGCAGGCGCAGGUUCCUUGAUGGCCAGCCUUGCUCAAGAGUGAGUAGUGGCCCAGAUGAGAUGUGGGUGAAUACUAGGUUUCCUGUUUACCUUUUCUCAUCAGCCUUUUGCAAUGAUUCAGGGUCAUAUGAGGGUACUGAAGAUUGGGUGAAUUAGACGUAUUCCUGAAAAGUAGGACUACAGAAGAGUGAUUGACGUGGAAAGUAAAUACCAAAAUCAAGAGGAUGAAGCAUGAAAGAAAGAGAUCCAGAGGUAAAGGAAAACCUCUGUGUGGACACAGAUCAAAGCAUUGCAAAGGCGUGUUGCUCAGAUGGGCCUUCCCCAAGAAAGAAAUCUGGCUUCUCCAUGCUGUGGAGGUGCCAGCAACCUGCAGUUGGACCCCACUGUGGCAACUAGAGGGUUCUGUGAAUAGCUAUCAGAGCAGCCUGUUAAGAAGGGAGCAGGGACCCCAGAUAUGCUAGGAAGGGGAGUCAGCCCAACUGAUCAGGGGUACACGUGAGCAAGAAGAGAACAGGGAAGAAUCUUUAGGAUUUCCUGCAGAAAAUGGAAACAUCUCACAGCACAAGUGAUGAUGCCAUCAUUUCUUCUUCCUUGUGGUUAGGACCCUGGGAGAAAGGGAUUCUGAUUUCUGAACUGAGGCAACAGAGUGAUGGACUUGGAACACAGAGUGAGAUCUGGGAAGAUUGUGUUUGCUCAGAGAUGAGCUGGCCUAAUAGGAGAGUUUUUUUAUUCUUGUUUUUAUUUUCUUUAUUUACUCAUUUGCAUCAGUGUAGGAAAUAUACUCCCACAAUUCAAAAAUCAAGUGUUCAAAAGGGUAUAUAGCAAAAGGUCUCUUUCAACACCUGUCCUCCAGUCAGCAGUCAGGAAGCAGUGCCAUCAGUUUGUAUCCGUCCAGAGUUAUAUUAUGUGUGGACAAGUACAUUCAUGUGGAUACACACAGACACACACACUUUCCCUCAUUUUUAUACAAAUGUACACUAUUCUAGACCUUUCUUUUUAAAUUUAGCAGUCUUGGAGUUCUUUUUACACCAAGUAUGUUUUUUAAAACUUCCUCAUUCAUAUCUAUGUCUGCAUAUUGUUCUACCAUCCAACAAUAGCCUAAUUUAUUUAAUCAGUCGUCUCUCAGUGGACAUUUAGGUGGUUUCCAAGUUUCUGCUAUUACAAAUAAUGCUGUAGUGAAUAAUCUUGUAUAUAUGUAAAGAUAUUGAUGUGGAAUUUAUGGGUCAAGGAGUACAUGAACUUGAAAUUUUGACAGAUAUUUCCAAAUUGCCCUCUCUAGAACAUAGAGGUUAUAUUCCCAUGAGCAAUGUAAUGUAUAUAAACUGAGCCUGAAAAAAGAAAGAACUAAGUAAAAUUGUGUACAAGAUUAACAGGUAAGAUGGAAUUGGAAACAACUGUGAUUAUGGGAGGUGCCCAGUAGUUUCACAUAGAAAAGAACCAUAAAGAAGAACUUUAAUGGUUGGCAAAGUGUGAUUAAAAAACAAAGUGAGCUGAGGUUAAAACACAGGACAGCAAUUAUAACCUCAUAAAUGCCACCUAGACAUCAUGAUGUGGAACCCAGAAUGGAACAGAGCUACAAAAGGGUCUGCUUUAUGGGAGGGAAACAGACCUGUUAGGAGGUGGGCCAGCCCUGGAGAUAAAGAAUUAUGAAGCUAGGCCAGGUGUGGUGGCUCAUGCCUGUAAUCCCAGUACUUUGGGAGGCUGAGGAGACUGGAUCACUUGAGGUCAGGAGUUUGAGGUCAGCCUGGCCAACAUAGUGAAACCCCAUCUCUACUAAAACAUACAAAAAUUAGCCAGGCAUGGUGGUACACACUUGUAGUCCAGCUACUUGGGAGACUGAGACAUGAGAAUUGCUUGAACCUGGGAGGUGGAGGUUGCAGUGAGCCGAGAUCGUGCCACUGCACUCCAGCCUGGGAGACAGAGUGAGACUCCGUCUCAAAAAAAAAAAAAAAAAAGAAUUAUAAAGCUAAGUUGAAAUGCCAAGCCUGUGGACAGACAUACCAGAAAACAAUGACAACACAUGGCUCAGGAGAAUUAAGGCAGAGUAGCCCAGAAGUUUUGGGUACACCACACACUGAGCAGAGGGAUGAAAAUAGAUGUGUUCCUGAUGCAGGUCUCCAAACUGACUGAUGCACACAAGGGGCAGUAAUGGAGGGAGGGGAGUAGCAACCUAUUUGUUAGCUCCUAAAUAUCUCCCAGCUGAAUUCUGAAGCAUUUGAAUGUUUACUUGUUUGUUUUUCUCACUUGCUUUCACUCUACUCAGAGGGUAGAAGACAAAACUAGGAAAACUGCCUUUCUAGCUCCAACAUUGAAGCAAAAGGAGAAACUGGUUUAUGAAGUAAAAGUGAUAGGUACCUUGAGAGAAAGUGGUCAUUGUUAUUUGAAUGUUCACGAGAGUGAGCAUGGAAAAACUAGGCAUAAACAGACAUGCACUGUAGACUUGGGUAAAUCAUAACUCUGACAAUUUAAAAAUAAAAUGGAUGGGGAACUGUCGAAUAGAGGAAGACCCAAGAAUAUUGAACUACUUAAAUAUAAUUCUGACUGUGCAAUCUCACAGAUAAUACCAAUAAAAAGGAAGAGUUUAGAGGUCUCUUGAAAGGAAGUAGUUUUCAGAGGGGCUUCUACAAAAGGCAGAAAGGACAUAUGCUAAAGACAAAAGUGCACCUGCAUGACCAGUGUCAGGAAGGGGACAUCCGAAACUAAAGGACAAUGCUGAGGACAACACAAAGCCAUACACACACAUACACACGCACACACAAACACCCACACACAGUUAUGUUCUUAAAAAGAAAAAAUGGACUUGAUUCCAUGGAUGCCUCUGACAGAUACAAAAAAUUUAGGACAAUAGUCCCCCAAAGUGCUUGCUAUAAGUUAAUUUUAAGGAAUCAGGAAAAUCAAAUGAGUUGCUAGAAAACUGGAAAUGAACCAUUUCCUUCUUGAUUUUCAAAAUGGCAAAAGUUUGAUAGAUUCAGUAAAUUUUAGUCUGUUGAGUUUGGGGCCAACUCUAUGAUGGUUUGCAAGAAGGGAGGAGACAAAGUAGGGAUCCGUGUCCUCAAGGAGUGAGUCUCGUCAGAUUGGCCUUAUCGGUUUGGCCGGGAAUGUGUCGUGUGGUAGACCAGGUAAAUCCACAUUUCAGUGAAGUGUUGCAAAAACGUUGCUUGAGAUAAUCUUGUAGACAGGAUGGAGGAAUAGAAGAUGAAUAUACUGAAAUAGGCAUAUUGAUGCCUGAGUUCAGGGUUUGGGUACAUAUUGUCAUGGAUAAGUGUGAUGUGUGCCAUAUGUCCCCUGUGCAUAGGUGCUGACACGUUGGGUGUUUGGGUAAGGGGAGUCGGUGUGUGUAUCAUGCAUAUGUGGAGAGAGGACGUGUUUGUGUGUGUGCCCCAGUGUGCACCCAUCUCUGCUAUUGCUUCUGCUUGGAUGAAGAGUUUCUUCUAGACUCCAUGCCUCGGUGUUGACACAACAAUAUGGCACAAAGGAGCUGUUGGGGAUUUGUUCGAACUGCAAGACAGGCAUCUGGAUGGGGCAGGCCUGAGGAAAAAUGCCAUGUCUUUUGGUUCUGUUGUGGAAAGUGGAGGGCCGUCGACAGUGACCACUGAGUGCCACCUGCUCCCUGCCCCAUGCACACUUCCUCUGUGCUGUUCUCUUAAGGAGUUCUGCGUCUGAGAGCUGUCUGACCUGGAGUGCUUUUCUCUUCUUUCUUUUCCUUCCUACAGUCGGUUCUGAAUGUGAUCAGUGAGCUGCAGGAGCAGAUGUGUAGGCUGCAGCUGGACAUCCACAGGCAGAUUCAAGAGCGCCUGUUACUCAGUAGGGACCACCCUGAGGAGGUGGCGGCCAGCGACGGUGUGGCCGAGCCCCAGCCCUGCAGCCAGGACUGUGCCUGUUGGGAGGGGUCACCUGAGUUACUGCAAGAGCUCAGGCACCUCAAAAUCAAAGUGGAAGAGUUGGAAAAUGAAAGGAAUCAGUAUGAAUGGAAGCUAAAGGCCACUAAGGCUGAAGUCGCCCAGCUGCAAGAACAGGUGGCCCUGAAAGAUGCAGAAAUUGAGCGUCUGCACAGCCAGCUCUCCCGGACAGCAGCUCUCCACAGUGAGAGUCACACAGAGAGAGACCAAGAAAUUCAACGUCUGAAAAUGGGGAUGGAAACUUUGCUGCUUGCCAAUGAAGAUAAGGACCGUCGGAUAGAGGAGCUUACGGGGCUGUUAAACCAGUACCGGAAGGUAAAGGAGAUUGUGAUGGUCACUCAAGGGCCUUCGGAGAGAACUCUCUCAAUCAAUGAAGAAGAACCGGAGGGAGGUUUCAGCAAGUGGAACGCUACAAAUAAGGACCCUGAAGAAUUAUUUAAACAAGAGAUGCCUCCAAGAUGUAGCUCUCCUACAGUGGGGCCACCUCCAUUGCCACAGAAAUCACUGGAAACCAGGGCUCAGAAAAAGCUCUCUUGUAGUCUAGAAGACUUGAGAAGUGAAUCUGUGGAUAAGUGUAUGGAUGGGAACCAGCCCUUCCCGGUGUUAGAACCCAAGGACAGCCCUUUCUUGGCGGAGCACAAAUAUCCCACUUUACCUGGGAAGCUUUCAGGAGCCACGCCCAAUGGAGAGGCUGCCAAAUCUCCUCCCACCAUCUGCCAGCCUGACGCCACGGGGAGCAGCCUGCUGAGGCUGAAUCGUGGCCGGAGUGUCAGUGCCCCCGUAUUAGGAGACACAGAAAGUGGCUGGGACGACACUGCUGUGGUCAAUGACCUCUCAUCCACAUCAUCGGGCACUGAAUCAGGUCCUCAGUCUCCUCUGACACCAGAUGGUAAACGGAAUCCCAAAGGCAUUAAGAAGUUCUGGGGAAAAAUCCGAAGAACUCAGUCAGGAAAUUUCUACACUGACACGCUGGGGAUGGCAGAGUUUCGACGAGGUGGGCUCCGGGCAACCGCAGGGCCAAGACUCUCUAGGACCAGGGACUCCAAGGGACAGAAAAGUGACGCCAAUGCCCCCUUUGCCCAGUGGAGCACAGAGCGUGUGUGUGCAUGGCUGGAGGACUUUGGCCUGGCUCAGUAUGUGAUCUUUGCCAGGCAGUGGGUAUCUUCUGGCCACACCUUAUUGACAGCCACCCCUCAGGACAUGGAAAAGGAGCUAGGAAUUAAGCACCCACUCCACAGGAAGAAGCUUGUUUUAGCAGUGAAAGCCAUCAACACCAAACAGGAGGAGAAGUCUGCACUGCUAGACCACAUUUGGGUGACAAGGUGGCUUGAUGAUAUUGGCUUACCCCAGUACAAAGACCAGUUUCAUGAAUCUAGAGUUGACAGACGAAUGCUGCAAUACCUAACUGUGAACGAUUUACUCUUCUUAAAAGUCACCAGCCAACUACAUCAUCUCAGCAUCAAAUGUGCCAUUCACGUGCUGCAUGUCAACAAGUUCAACCCCCACUGCCUGCACCGGCGGCCAGCUGAUGAGAGUAACCUUUCUCCUUCAGAAGUUGUACAGUGGUCCAACCACAGGGUGAUGGAGUGGUUACGAUCUGUGGACCUGGCAGAGUAUGCACCCAAUCUUCGAGGGAGUGGAGUCCAUGGAGGCCUCAUUAUCCUGGAGCCACGCUUCACUGGGGACACCCUGGCUAUGCUUCUCAACAUCCCCCCACAAAAGACGCUCCUCAGGCGCCACCUGACCACCAAGUUCAAUGCCUUGAUUGGUCCGGAGGCUGAACAGGAGAAGCGAGAGAAAAUGGCCUCACCAGCUUACACACCACUGACCACCACAGCCAAAGUCCGGCCAAGGAAACUAGGAUUUUCACACUUCGGAAACAUAAGAAAAAAGAAGUUCGAUGAAUCGACGGACUACAUUUGCCCAAUGGAGCCCAGUGACGGUGUCAGUGAUAGUCACAGGGUCUACAGUGGCUACCGGGGCCUCAGCCCCCUUGAUGCCCCUGAACUGGAUGGGCUGGACCAGAUGGCACCUUCGGAAGGUACCGUGACGCAGAUAGGGCUCCUCUCCCAAGACAUUCACCGCCUUACGACAAUGCUGAGCCAGGACCAGCUGCUGAAUGACUCUCGCCUGCCUGCCCCCAACUCUGAUGACUGGAGAUGACUUUCUUCGUGGCUGAGAGCGUAGGGAGGCAUGUGUGGGGGCCCCGGAGCCUUUGCUUCUGUGGGGAGCGGGCACACAGCCCCCUCUGCAAGCCCAGUCCGGGCUGGCAGGGUGUCUCAGACAGGCUGCUGACAGGCAUGAAGCAGAGCUGUGGGACAGGUGUCCAGGGGUGGCCCCAGGGUCCAUGUGUGUCUUCAACCAUGCUGCGCUCUUCACCGCAGGCUUCAUACCUUUUGUACUUUUAUACGUGGACUGCAGACCACUUUGUGGGAGGGCAGUGACAUAUCAGCACACAGACUCGAUGGCUCGUGAUAUUCCUGGUGACAGCCUGGAGGCUCUCACACUCGAGGGGAAGAGCUGUUAGUUCAUAAAACCUGCUGGAAAAAAAGUUCCGAAAAACUGUUUUGAAUGUUCUGUAGAGACUGUGUUUUGUGAAAUGGUCACCAGGAGGUCCCUCCGGGGCUGCUUCACAGAACGUGCUUUUUCCAUUCUUGGGACUGUGGCUGGGCAAGGCAGGUGUUUAGGGUAUGAGCGGGUAAAGCAACGAGGCUCCUUACCCACAGCACUGCCUGACUCUAUCUCCCGUCAUCUGCAAGGGGUAUCUGUGCGACUCCCAGCUUGGAGCAGAGGCGUCCCCAACACGUGCACACCCUGCCUUCUGCCUCCACCCAAGCUGACACACAGCCUCCUCCCAGGCCUUGCCCUUGGAGCAGCUCAGGCGUAAUGUCUGAUUAAAUAGCUCCCCCAAGUGGAAGGCCCUUGAGCACCUCAAGCUCCGUGUUUCCACCCCAACUCACCAACUUCCCAAACAUGUCUGUUUCCUCUCCACUCUUUAGUCCUUCCUCCCUCCAGGCGUCUGCUCAGGCCCUUCCCUCACUAGGGAAUGCAUUUUUCUCCUAGUCCCCUUCAUGAGGGAAAAUCCUGUCUCUCAAGGCACGGCAAAGAGACCAUCUCUCAGGAAGCCUUCCCGCAUGAUCCAGUUACAGGUAGCUCUCCCACAGUGCCGUGUCUGCCCUUGAGCCAGAGCACAGCUCACCUUGAAGUUUCUUGUCGUCUUACCAUACCCGUCCUCACCACAAACUUGGAGCACCUGCUCUGCACUGGCUCCUGUAGACAGUCCUCCAGUUGCCAAGGAGAUCUGUGCUCCUAAGUUCCUCAUCCACCCACUCCUUCGCAUGUGUGUGUUAAGAACCUUCCAUGCCAGGGCUAGAGAUACAGGCAUGAAUGCCAAGGUCCCUGCCUAAAGGUGCUUACAGUGUAGUGGAGUACAGACCAGUUUCAAACAAGACUCUGCCAAAGGUUACAGAUGCUCCAAUAUUAGUUUCUGCAGCCUAAAAGAGCAU